AGCCGAGCCUGCGGAAGGCGGCGGCGGCGGCACCUGCGAUCAGCGGCUGGGGCAGGUUAUGGUAGUGCGGACUGCGGUGUGAGCAGAGCGGCCACGGGGCCCGCCAUGCGCCGGCGGCCCUGACAUGGGCGCCAGCGGGUCCAAAGCUCGGGGCCUGUGGCCCUUCGCCUCGGCGGCCGGAGGCGGCGGCUCAGAGGCAGCAGGAGCUGAGCAAGCUUUGGUGCGGCCUCGGGGCCGAGCUGUGCCCCCCUUCGUAUUCACGCGCCGCGGCUCUAUGUUCUAUGAUGAGGAUGGGGAUCUGGCUCACGAGUUCUAUGAGGAGACAAUCGUCACCAAGAACGGGCAGAAGCGGGCCAAGCUGAGGCGAGUGCAUAAGAAUCUGAUUCCUCAGGGCAUCGUGAAGCUGGAUCACCCCCGCAUCCACGUGGAUUUCCCUGUGAUCCUCUAUGAGGUGUGACCCUGGGAGGUGGCAGACAGAAGCACCCCCUGCCCCGGCAAGAAACUCCCAGGCUCAAUCAAGGUGUGGCUUCCAUUGAGGAGCCCAGGCUGGGGCCACAACCCUGAAUAAACUCUGUUGGCCCAUAACCUUCAGCUGUGAGCGGGUCGGUCCCACAGUAUUGGUUGGGUGUUGGUUUGUGUGUGGACAAGAGGUGGUUGGUGGGUGGUGAAGGCUAAUGGCAGAGUUAGCACCCCACUCUCCCAAGCCACCCCUGCAAGCAGCACAGCAGGGCAUAUACCAGUCAGGAAUGCCCGUUACCUGGUUCCUUGCCUGGUCUGCUUUCUUCCAAGUUUGCCUGGGGCCUAGCCCUGCUAGAGGCUACAGCACUUUACAAGCAAGGUAUGCUUUCUUCCAGCCCCUAGGCUGUGGGCACUGUAUACAAGUAGGAACUUCCUUUCCUUCACUUCCCUUUUAACCCCUAGUCAGAGCAUUUCAGCCGUUUGCUACCUCGAUUCCUCCUGUGUUGGACAGAGGCUGGGGGCAGUGCCAGCCUGAUUCUUCCGACCUACCUGCCAUUUGUUCCCGCCUUCAGAUGGAUGGACAGUUUGCUGGCUAUUGAUAGGAGUGGGGACUGGGUGGGGGCUUCUCCCUCUACCCAGGGCUGGGCUGAUCCCCCUACUGCAACUAACUGUUGCCCCCCAACCCCGAACCCCCAGUUGAGGAGUUGAGAGAGUGCAGGCUGGGGUCAGGACAGGCUGCGGAUGCUUGUGCCUAUGGGGAGUUACUCCAACCCACCUAUUCUGUCUAAUCUCCAUGGCUUUGCACCAAAUCCUCCACCCCUCCAAUUGGGAGGGGACUGUUCACCACCUUGUGGUAAGGGACAACACCCUAAGGCUGGUGCCAGUAGUUAUGAGUAGCCUACCACCCCCUCCCUUACAGUAACCCCCACCCCUUCAGGAUCAGUCAAGGGAAAGCACUAGAACCCCUGGGUAGGGAAAGAAAGGAGGGAAAAACCAUAAAAGGAAUACUUAUAAUGUGAAGGUUUGUAAAUAGUCCAUGAUGAUGUCGUGGCAGAGUCUGAUUUCUAUAUAGAGGUGACUUUUUUUUUAAGUACUGUGCAAGCUCUGUGCUUCUAUAAUGUGGGAAAUGGCUUGGGGAGGAUGGCCCCUAGCUUAGGAAGACUGUUGUGUUAUUUGUUCAAUUUCAAUAAAAUGAUUUGUAGAUCCUGCA